AUCCCAGGUUAGCUGCUGCGAGCCGAGCCGGGCGGCGGAGGCGGCGGCGGCGGCGGCAGUGGCGGCAGUGGCGGCAGUGGCGGCAGCGGCAGCAGUUGCAGCAGUGGUGGCCAGAGCGGAUGCUUGCGGGCUCCCUGCGGCUCCACUAGUUUUCUUCGCCCCGCCCAGCCGCCCACUCUUCUCGGCUAGGGAAGAAGACCAGAGGGUGCUCAGCUGGAAAACUCUGGUGUCUCAGCUUAGGGCCUCCUCCGGGAAGAGCUAACUGCUCCCAGGUGAAGCCGGUGCCCGCGGGCGGUCCGUACACCCCGCAGCCGGCUCGCACCGCUCGAGAGCCUCGGCCGCUGUGUCUUCCACGUCUGCAGCUCAGCCAGGGCGCGCAGGGCGAGUGGGGUCCACUGGCGGGUAAAGGGGACCAGGACGGCGAGGAUGGACGCACAGACCUGGCCCGUGGGCUUUCGCUGCCUCCUCCUUCUGGCCCUGGUUGGGUCCGCCCGCAGCGAGGGCGUGCAGACCUGCGAAGAAGUUCGGAAACUUUUCCAGUGGCGGCUGCUGGGAGCUGUCAGGGGGCUGCCGGAUUCGCCGCGGGCAGGACCUGAUCUUCAGGUUUGCAUAUCCAAAAAGCCUACAUGUUGCACCAGGAAGAUGGAGGAGAGAUAUCAGAUUGCGGCUCGCCAGGAUAUGCAGCAGUUUCUUCAAACGUCCAGCUCUACAUUAAAGUUUCUAAUAUCUCGAAAUGCGGCUGCUUUUCAAGAAACCCUUGAAACUCUCAUCAAACAAGCAGAAAAUUACACCAGUAUACUUUUUUGCAGUACCUACAGGAACAUGGCCUUGGAGGCUGCUGCUUCGGUUCAGGAGUUCUUCACUGAUGUGGGGCUGUAUUUAUUUGGUGCGGAUGUUAAUCCUGAAGAAUUUGUAAACAGAUUUUUUGACAGUCUUUUUCCUCUGGUCUACAACCACCUCAUUAACCCUGGUGUGACUGACAGUUCCCUGGAAUACUCAGAAUGCAUCCGGAUGGCUCGCCGGGAUGUGAGUCCAUUUGGUAAUAUUCCCCAAAGAGUAAUGGGACAGAUGGGGAGGUCCCUGCUGCCCAGCCGCACUUUUCUGCAGGCACUCAAUCUGGGCAUUGAAGUCAUCAACACCACAGACUAUCUGCACUUCUCCAAAGAGUGCAGCAGAGCCCUCCUGAAGAUGCAAUACUGCCCGCACUGCCAAGGCCUGGCGCUCACUAAGCCUUGUAUGGGAUACUGCCUCAAUGUCAUGCGAGGCUGCCUGGCGCACAUGGCGGAGCUUAAUCCACACUGGCAUGCAUAUAUCCGGUCGUUGGAAGAACUCUCGGAUGCAAUGCAUGGAACAUACGACAUUGGACACGUGCUGCUGAACUUUCACUUGCUUGUUAAUGAUGCUGUGUUACAGGCUCACCUCAAUGGACAAAAAUUAUUGGAACAGGUAAAUAGGAUUUGUGGCCGCCCUGUAAGAACACCCACACAAAGCCCCCGUUGUUCUUUUGAUCAGAGCAAAGAGAAGCAUGGAAUGAAGACCACCACAAGGAACAGUGAAGAGACGCUUGCCAACAGAAGAAAAGAAUUUAUCAACAGCCUUCGACUGUACAGGUCAUUCUAUGGAGGUCUAGCUGAUCAGCUUUGUGCUAAUGAAUUAGCUGCUGCAGAUGGACUUCCCUGCUGGAAUGGAGAAGAUAUAGUAAAAAGUUGGCAGGUUUCGAGCUGGGGAGAUGAUGGAUCAAAAGUGAGAAAGAAGAAGUGAGAGAAGAAAUCAUUCUUUGUGACUGGUAAUUUUAUGAUCUCUCAUUGAUGUUUUCUAGCCUGGCAGGUAUUAACAGCUGAUGCCCUAGUGCUUUUGUGUGCUUAAGACAAUGUCUCUCCCCUCUAUUUCUCCAUGUGAUGGUAAUGUUUUGGCCUCUUUCUGCUGAGAUCUUUUGGUGGGUUCCUUUUCUCCCAUAUCAUCUAUUCUAGCCCAUAGAAACCUUCCCUCUCUUUUCUACUUUUGGUGGAAGUACAGCCUACACCUAAUGCAGCUGCCUCUCUUUACUCUGCCACUAGACAGCCAACUUCUGCUACAAGAAUGGGCUGCCUUCCAUUUGCGUAGGCAUAGGCCAACUACCAGCCCUUUUAGUCCUUCCAGCUCCAAGGAUCCUUCAACACUUCUCUCACCUAGGACCAAUGAAUGAGGGAAUGCCGUAGCAGUUCAAUCAGCUUUCUUCAAACAAGUUCCCUGCUUUGUUCUCUUCAACUUCAAUCCUUUUAUUCAAUUAAGGUGGAUGUCAAACUGUGGGACUGAAAACAAGGUUUCAGUCAUCUGCUUUUCAUGUCUAGCACCUCACUGAAAGUGAGGGGUGUAUGCCAUCUAUUGUCCCUUGUUCUUGGCUGAAAUGGAAACAGAAAGAGUACUAUUUUAGCACCCUUUUCCAUGUACUUGGAAGUGGUGCAGAGAAGACAGAAAACUAGUUUCCAAAUUCAAGAUACUGCAAUAGACCUUGAAUGGAACGCAAAGUUAUAUGAGAUAUUUUCCCAAUCUUUCAGGGACUUGGAAUCUCAAACUGGUAGAAAACAUGUUCACAAAACACAUUCACAGCAAAACAGGUUUUGAAAUAAAAGAAGUGUACAAUCCCACAGACUUUCAAAUAGGGGAAAAUUCUUUUUUGAUUGAGAGGAUUCAACAGUAUUUAAUGAAAGAGGUAAUAUGUGAUAUGAGUUUUCAUUCAAUUAAAAUAAAUUCUUUAAAAUAUGGAUGAGAUGAGAUAAUGACUGAGAAUGCUUUAAAAUAAUUCAGUGAGUGGGAGAAAGAGGGUCAUAUUAUAUUUGAAGUGAAGUUUUCUGAGUGAGUAAUCAUUGAAGCUGUUUGAUGGGAACGGAGUGUUAUACUAUAUUUUCUGUAUAUUUGUAUUCACUUAAAAUUCUGUAAUACAUAAAUACAAAAAUAUAGUAACACAAUAAAAAUAACUUUGUCACUGUCUACUCUUUCACAAACACUGUUCUAGAUGCUAGGGACACAGUGAUGGACAAAAUAGACAUAAGUCCAUCUCUCAUGUAGACUAGGAUAUAGAAGAGAAGAACACAGAACAAAUAUUUACAAGUGGGAAUAGUUUACAAAAUCUUUCAAGUUGGAUGGAAUUUUAAUCAGCAGACUUGGAAGCAAGAAAGCGAGUGGGAGCAAAUGCAUUCUUGAGUGAAAUGCUCUGAGUUGAGUGGCCUCUACACUGCAUUACUUUCAUUUGUGUACAAACUUUCAGAUUAUGUUUUCUCCUUCUCACUAUUCUCUUUCAUUUCAGCUUCAUGGGCAUGUCGUGACUAUUUAGUAUUAGAAGCCUUCUCUCAUUCAUUAUAAUGCAACCAUUCAUUCAUAAAGCCAAUAAGGCUCAGUGGUUAGGAACAGGUUCAGGAGCCAUGCUACUAAGGUUGUCAAUAAAGAUUAACCACUUACCAGUGAUGUGAAUUAAGACAUAUUCAUUAAUCUCUAAGUGCAUCACUUUUCUUAACUUUAAAAUGUGGGUAAGGCCGGGCGCGGUGGCUCAUGCCUGUAAUCCCAGCGCUUCGGGAGGCUGAGGUGGGCAGAACACGAGGUCAGGAGUUCGAGACCAGCCUGACCAACAUGGUGAAACCCUGUCUCUACUAAAAAUACAAAAUUAACUGUGUGUGGUGGCACAUGCCUGUAAUCUCAGCUACUUAUGUGGCUGAGGCAGGAAAAUUGCUUGAACCCGGGAGGUGGAGGUUGCAGUGAGCCGAGACUGCACCACUGCACUCCAGCCUGGGUGACAGAGAGAGACUUUAUCUCAAAAAAGAAAAAAGUAGGUGAAAGUAAUACCUACCUAAUAUUUGAAAAUUAAAUGAGUUAUUCACAUGAACAGUUUAGAAUCCUAGAUAUAACAUAGUCAAUAACUGUUAAAUCAUGUUAUUGUUAAAUAAAAUAUGCUCAUUUACUUCAAUGGAAAUGAAACUAUUGUAUUGACAUUUUCUCUUCAUUGGAUGGGUUCUGUCUUGGAUUAGAAGACUUCCAUUUGUAAGACAAAGGCAUAUGCAUUCUUGAGUGAAAUGCUCUGAGUUUAGUGGCCUCUAGUGAAGUUUCUUUUAUGAGUUAAUAAAAAUUAGUAUUAGGGAUUUGGGUUUGGGAAUAGGAGAUAUUCCCAUAUCAAUACUUUAAAUGGUUAUUUUGUUGGAUCUGAAAACUGAGAAAUUAUGUCUUAAUGGGCAGUUCAUCAGAUACUCCAAACUGGAGAGUGAUAGUCACUUGAACCCAUGCACUAUAUCAGUGUUUUCAAGGGAGAACUGAAAGUUAAGAUACAAAGAUAAAGCACUAUAGAGAUAAAAGUAAAAUGCUUAUUUCUAACCAGUGGUUUGGGAAUGUUCACUCACUGGUUAGUCUUAGAGCUGAUCUUAAUGAACUAUCAGUUGAUUGGAAAUAAAUUUCUGAAGCCAGGCUAAAUUUCAGUGUAUCACACAACAGAUUGUUUUGGGUGACACGGCAAUUUCAACGCUGCUACAAUUCUAGUCAUCUCCCUUUAUCCACUGAGUUCCCAAAGGAAAUAGGUAUUUUAAACAGAAUCCCUAGGAAAAAAUGAGGUUAAACAUCCGCUUUUCCCAUGUGUCUACUCAGUUUCUUGCCAUGCUGACACAGUAUGAGGAUACUAUUUUUAACUUGUUACACGCGUCCAGAGGUUGAAUAGAGGAAGAUAAAAAGAUAAAAGAUAGCAAGAUAAAAGUUCACUGAAGUGGAAACCUAAAGGACCUUUUCCCAUCUGUUUGGCACAGAAGUUGUUAUCUCUUUGGGAGUACAGAUUUCAUCACAGUUCUAUAGACUUGUGACUUCCAGAUUGUGUAAUUGCAAAACAGCAGCAGUCUUCAAGGCUCCAGGAUGCCUGUUCUUACUUUAGCCAGAGCAGUUUCUUAUUCAUCCUUCGUUUUCAUAUUGAGGUUACACCUGAAAAGCUAUUCCCUUUUCAGUUAAAUGGAUGUAAGUUUGCUAAACUACAAAAAUGGAAAAUAUUGUUUAUUAGUCUAGUUCCAGUGUUUCCAUAUCAUAGCAUAUAAAUUCACUGUUGAAUGAUUUAUUAUAUAUUAAAGUAAAAUGCUAGAAGGGAGAUUGGAAAAGAACAGGCACCUAUUCAUAAUAUAUUUUUCUUCAAAUAGACUACAGUGUAGUCUAAUUGAAUUUAUAAGAAUAGCUCAUCAGAUAGCACAUUUUAUUGUCCAACCAUCCAAAUCCUUCUUUUCUGAUGUAUUUUUCAACCCAAACAAAGGAAAUUUGUUGGAUAUUAUUGAAAAAACUUCUACAAAAUUUGAUUUGAAAUUAUUUUUACAUUAAUGCCACAUUUUGGCUUACAUGAUUAAUAUUUUUUGUGUGGCUGCAAUUAUGUAUAAAACUGAUUAAAGAUCAAACUCUGAAAGUAGAUUGUCUAAACACACACACAAAAAUAAUUCGCAUGCAUUACUUCUUCAGGAAAAUAAAGAAAUAAAAAUAUUUUCUUAUUUCAGAGUAGUCAUGAAGAAAUGAAAUAUUCAGAAAAAUGAAAAGUAUAAUUAUAUGUGUGAAAUAUUGUUCAUUUUUGGAUUAUUCUAGACAGAAUCUAGACCUUUUUAGUUAUAUUAGAUCAUUAAACCAACAACAGUUUAGAAUAAAUACGGUUAAAUUAUUUGGUACCAAAUAAAAAUAUCAUGUUUAUAACAAGCAAUGUAUAUUUAAAUAUAACAAGUAUUGCUAUUUACUAAAA